GCAACCCACACCGCCCCUGCCAGCCACCAUGGGGCUGCCACUAGCCCGCCUGGCGGCUGUGUGCCUGGCCCUGUCUUUGGCAGGGGGCUCGGAGCUCCAGACAGAGGGCAGAACCCGAAACCACGGCCACAACGUCUGCAGCACCUGGGGCAACUUCCACUACAAGACCUUCGACGGGGACGUCUUCCGCUUCCCCGGCCUCUGCGACUACAACUUCGCCUCCGACUGCCGAGGCUCCUACAAGGAAUUUGCUGUGCACCUGAAGCGGGGUCCGGGCCAGGCUGAGGCCCCCGCCGGGGUGGAGUCCAUCCUGCUGACCAUCAAGGAUGACACCAUCUACCUCACCCGCCACCUGGCUGUGCUUAACGGGGCCGUGGUCAGCACCCCGCACUACAGCCCCGGGCUGCUCAUUGAGAAGAGCGAUGCCUACACCAAAGUCUACUCCCGCGCCGGCCUCACCCUCAUGUGGAACCGGGAGGAUGCACUCAUGCUGGAGCUGGACACUAAGUUCCGGAACCACACCUGUGGCCUCUGCGGGGACUACAACGGCCUGCAGAGCUAUUCAGAAUUCCUCUCUGACGGCGUGCUCUUCAGUCCCCUGGAGUUUGGGAACAUGCAGAAGAUCAACCAGCCCGAUGUGGUGUGUGAGGAUCCCGAGGAGGAGGUGGCCCCCGCAUCCUGCUCCGAGCACCGCGCCGAGUGUGAGAGGCUGCUGACCGCCGAGGCCUUCGCGGACUGUCAGGACCUGGUGCCGCUGGAGCCGUAUCUGCGCGCCUGCCAGCAGGACCGCUGCCGGUGCCCGGGCGGUGACACCUGCGUCUGCAGCACCGUGGCCGAGUUCUCCCGCCAGUGCUCCCACGCCGGCGGCCGGCCCGGGAACUGGAGGACCGCCACGCUCUGCCCCAAGACCUGCCCCGGGAACCUGGUGUACCUGGAGAGCGGCUCGCCCUGCAUGGACACCUGCUCACACCUGGAGGUGAGCAGCCUGUGCGAGGAGCACCGCAUGGACGGCUGUUUCUGCCCAGAAGGCACCGUAUAUGACGACAUCGGGGACAGUGGCUGCGUUCCUGUGAGCCAGUGCCACUGCAGGCUGCACGGACACCUGUACACACCGGGCCAGGAGAUCACCAAUGACUGCGAGCAGUGUGUCUGUAACGCUGGCCGCUGGGUGUGCAAAGACCUGCCCUGCCCCGGCACCUGUGCCCUGGAAGGCGGCUCCCACAUCACCACCUUCGAUGGGAAGACGUACACCUUCCACGGGGACUGCUACUAUGUCCUGGCCAAGGGUGACCACAACGAUUCCUACGCUCUCCUGGGCGAGCUGGCCCCCUGUGGCUCCACAGACAAGCAGACCUGCCUGAAGACGGUGGUGCUGCUGGCUGACAAGAAGAAGAAUGUGGUGGUCUUCAAGUCCGAUGGCAGUGUACUGCUCAACGAGCUGCAGGUGAACCUGCCCCACGUGACCGCGAGCUUCUCUGUCUUCCGCCCGUCUUCCUACCACAUCAUGGUGAGCAUGGCCAUUGGCGUCCGGCUGCAGGUGCAGCUGGCCCCAGUCAUGCAACUCUUUGUGACACUGGACCAGGCCUCCCAGGGGCAGGUGCAGGGCCUCUGCGGGAACUUCAACGGCCUGGAAGGUGACGACUUCAAGACGGCCAGCGGGCUGGUGGAGGCCACGGGGGCCGGCUUUGCCAACACCUGGAAGGCACAGUCAAGCUGCCAUGACAAGCUGGACUGGUUGGACGAUCCCUGCUCCCUGAACAUCGAGAGCGCCAACUACGCCGAGCACUGGUGCUCCCUCCUGAAGAAGACAGAGACCCCCUUUGGCAGGUGCCACUCGGCUGUGGACCCUGCUGAGUAUUACAAGAGGUGCAAAUAUGACACGUGUAACUGUCAGAACAAUGAGGACUGCCUGUGCGCCGCCCUGUCCUCCUACGCGCGCGCCUGCACCGCCAAGGGCGUCAUGCUGUGGGGCUGGCGGGAGCAUGUCUGCAACAAGGAUGUGGGCUCCUGCCCCAACUCGCAGGUCUUCCUGUACAACCUGACCACCUGCCAGCAGACCUGCCGCUCCCUCUCCGAGGCCGACAGCCACUGUCUCGAGGGCUUUGCGCCUGUGGACGGCUGCGGCUGCCCUGACCACACCUUCCUGGACGAGAAGGGCCGCUGCGUACCCCUGGCCAAGUGCUCCUGUUACCACCGCGGUCUCUACCUGGAGGCGGGGGAUGUGGUCGUCAGGCAGGAAGAACGAUGUGUGUGCCGGGAUGGGCGGCUGCACUGUAGGCAGAUCCGGCUGAUCGGCCAGAGCUGCACGGCCCCAAAGAUCCACAUGGACUGCAGCAACCUGACUGCACUGGCCACCUCGAAGCCCCGAGCCCUCAGCUGCCAGACGCUGGCCGCCGGCUAUUACCACACAGAGUGUGUCAGUGGCUGUGUGUGCCCCGACGGGCUGAUGGAUGACGGCCGGGGUGGCUGCGUGGUGGAGAAGGAAUGCCCUUGCGUCCAUAACAACGACCUGUAUUCUUCCGGCGCCAAGAUCAAGGUGGACUGCAAUACCUGCACCUGCAAGAGAGGACGCUGGGUGUGCACCCAGGCUGUGUGCCAUGGCACCUGCUCCAUUUACGGGAGUGGCCACUACAUCACCUUUGAUGGGAAGUACUACGACUUUGACGGACACUGCUCCUACGUGGCUGUUCAGGACUACUGCGGCCAGAACUCCUCACUGGGCUCAUUCAGCAUCAUCACCGAGAACGUCCCCUGUGGCACUACGGGCGUCACCUGCUCCAAGGCCAUCAAGAUCUUCAUGGGGAGGACGGAGCUGAAGUUGGAAGACAAGCACCGUGUGGUGAUCCAGCGUGAUGAGGGUCACCACGUGGCCUACACCACGCGGGAGGUGGGCCAGUACCUGGUGGUGGAGUCCAGCACGGGCAUCAUCGUCAUCUGGGACAAGAGGACCACCGUGUUCAUCAAGCUGGCUCCCUCCUACAAGGGCACCGUGUGUGGCCUGUGUGGGAACUUUGACCACCGCUCCAACAACGACUUCACCACGCGGGACCACAUGGUGGUGAGCAGCGAGCUGGACUUCGGGAACAGCUGGAAGGAGGCCCCCACCUGCCCAGAUGUGAGCACCAACCCCGAGCCCUGCAGCCUGAACCCGCACCGCCGCUCCUGGGCCGAGAAGCAGUGCAGCAUCCUCAAAAGCAGCGUGUUCAGCAUCUGCCACAGCAAGGUGGACCCCAAGCCCUUCUACGAGGCCUGUGUGCACGACUCGUGCUCCUGUGACACGGGUGGGGACUGUGAGUGCUUCUGCUCUGCCGUGGCCUCCUACGCCCAGGAGUGUACCAAAGAGGGGGCCUGCGUGUUCUGGAGGACGCCGGACCUGUGCCCCAUAUUCUGCGACUACUACAACCCUCCGCAUGAGUGUGAGUGGCACUAUGAGCCAUGUGGGAACCGGAGCUUCGAGACCUGCAGGACCAUCAACGGCAUCCACUCCAACAUCUCCGUGUCCUACCUGGAGGGCUGCUACCCCCGGUGCCCCAAGGACAGGCCCAUCUAUGAGGAGGAUCUGAAGAAGUGUGUCACUGCAGACAAGUGUGGCUGCUAUGUCGAGGACACCCACUACCCACCUGGAGCAUCGGUUCCCACCGAGGAGACCUGCAAGUCCUGCGUGUGUACCAACUCCUCCCAAGUCGUCUGCAGGCCGGAGGAAGGAAAGAUUCUUAACCAGACCCAGGAUGGCGCCUUCUGCUACUGGGAGAUCUGUGGCCCCAACGGGACGGUGGAGAAGCACUUCAACAUCUGUUCCAUUACGACACGCCCGUCCACCCUGACCACCUUCACCACCAUCACCCUCCCCACCACCCCCACCACCUUCACCACUACCACCACCACCACCACCCCGACCUCCAGCACAGUUUUAUCAACAACUCCGAAGCUGUGCUGCCUCUGGUCUGACUGGAUCAAUGAGGACCACCCCAGCAGUGGCAGCGACGACGGUGACCGAGAAACAUUUGAUGGGGUCUGCGGGGCCCCUGAGGACAUCGAGUGCAGGUCGGUCAAGGAUCCCCACCUCAGCUUGGAGCAGCUAGGCCAGAAGGUGCAGUGUGAUGUCUCUGUUGGGUUCAUUUGCAAGAAUGAAGACCAGUUUGGAAAUGGACCAUUUGGACUGUGUUACGACUACAAGAUACGUGUCAAUUGUUGCUGGCCCAUGGAUAAGUGUAUCACCACUCCCAGCCCUCCAACUACCACUCCCAGCCCUCCACCAACCAGCACGACCACCCUUCCACCAACCACCACCCCCAGCCCUCCAACCACCACCACAACCACCCCUCCACCAACCACCACCCCCAGCCCUCCAAUAACCACCACGACCACCCCUCCACCAACCACCACUCCCAGCCCUCCAAUAAGCACCACAACCACCCCUCCACCAACCACCACUCCCAGCCCUCCAACCACCACUCCCAGCCCUCCAACCACCACUCCCAGCCCUCCAACAACCACCACAACCACCCCUCCACCAACCACCACUCCCAGCCCUCCAACGACUACGCCCAUCACUCCACCAGCCAGCACUACCACCCUUCCACCAACCACCACUCCCAGCCCUCCAACAACCACCACAACCACCCCUCCACCAACCACCACUCCCAGUCCUCCAACGACUACGCCCAUCACUCCACCAACCAGCACUACUACCCUUCCACCAACCACCACUCCCAGCCCUCCACCAACCACCACAACCACCCCUCCACCAACCACCACUCCCAGCCCUCCAACAACCACCACUCCCAGUCCUCCAACAAUCACCACAACCACCCCUCCACCAACCACCACUCCCAGCCCUCCAACAACGACCACAACCACCCCUCCACCAACCACCACUCCCAGCCCUCCAACGACUACACCCAUCACUCCACCAACCAGCACUACCACCCUUCCACCAACCACCACUCCCAGCCCUCCACCAACCACCACAACCACCCCUCCACCAACCACCACUCCCAGCCCUCCAACAACCACCACUCCCAGCCCUCCAAUAACCACCACAACCACCCCUCCACCAACCACCACUCCCAGCUCUCCAAUAACCACCACUCCCAGCCCUCCAACAACCACCAUGACCACCCCUUCACCAACCACCACCCCCAGCUCUCCAAUAACCACCACAACCACCCCUUCCUCAACUACCACUCCCAGCCCUCCACCAACCACCAUGACCACCCCUUCACCAACCACCACUCCCAGCCCUCCAACAACCACCACGACCACCCUUCCACCAACCACCACUUCCAGCCCUCUAACAACUACUCCUCUACCUCCAUCAAUAACUCCUCCUACAUUUUCACCAUUCUCAACGACAACCCCUACUACCCCAUGCGUGCCUCUCUGCAAUUGGACUGGCUGGCUGGAUUCUGGAAAACCCAACUUUCACAAACCAGGUGGAGACACAGAAUUGAUUGGAGACGUCUGUGGACCAGGCUGGGCAGCUAACAUCUCUUGCAGAGCCACCAUGUAUCCUGAUGUUCCCAUUGGACAGCUUGGACAAACAGUGGUGUGUGAUGUCUCUGUGGGGCUGAUAUGCAAAAAUGAAGACCAAAAGCCAGGUGGGGUCAUCCCUAUGGCCUUCUGCCUCAACUACGAGAUCAACGUUCAGUGCUGUGAGUGUGUCACCCAACCCACCACCAUGACAACCACCACCACAGAGAACCCAACUCCGACACCAAUCACCACCACCACUACGGUGACCCCAACCCCAACACCCACCAGCACACAGAGUACAACACCAACACCCAUCACCACCACCAAUACGGUAACCCCAACCCCAACCCCCACUGGCACACAGACCCCAACCCCGACACCCAUCACCACCACCACCACUAUGGUGACCCCAACCCCAACAAUCACCAGCACACAGACCCCAACCCCGACACCCAUCACCACCACUACGGUGACCCCAACCCCAACACCCACCAGCACACAGAGAACAACACCGACAUCCAUCACCACCACCACCACGGUGACCCCAACCCCAACACCCACCGGCACACAGACCCCAACCACGACACCCAUCACCACCACCACCACGGUGACCCCAACCCCAACACCCACCGGCACACAGACCCCAACAACGACACCCAUCAGCACCACCACCACGGUGACCCCAACCCCAACACCCACUGGAACACAGACCCUAACCCCAACACCCAUCACCACCACCACUACGGUGACCCCAACCCCUACACCCACCGGCACACAGACCCCAACAUCGACACCCAUCACCACCACCACUACGGUGACCCCAACACCAACACCCACUGGCACACAGACCCCAACCCUGACACCCAUCACCACCACCACUACGGUGACCCCAACCCCAACACCCACCGGCACACAGACCCCAACCACGACACCCAUCACCACCACCACUACGGUGACCCCAACCCCAACACCCACCGGCACAAAGAGUACAACCCCGACAUCCAUCACCACCACCACUAUGGUGACCCCAACCCCACCACCCACUGGCACACAGACCCCAACCACGACACCCAUCACCACCACCACUACGGUGACCCCAACCCCAACACCCACCGGCACACAGACCCCAACCCCGACACCCAUCACCACCACCACCACGGUGACCCCAACCCCAACACCCACCGGCACACAGACCCCAACAUCGACACCCAUCACCACCAACACUACGGUGACCCCAACCCCAACACCAACCGGCACACCGAGUACAACCCUGACACCCAUCACCACCACCACUACGGUGACCCCAACCCCAACACCCACCGGCACACAGACCCCAACAUCGACACCCAUCAGCACCACCACUAUGGUGACCCCAACCCCAACACCCACCGGCACACAGACCCCAACCCCUACACCCAUCUCCACCACCACUACGGUGACCCCAACCCCAACACCCACCGGCACACAGACCCCAACCCCGACACCCAUCACCACCACCACCACGGUGACCCCAACCCCAACACCCACCGGCACACAGACCCCAACAUCGACACCCAUCACCACCACCACUACGGUGACCCCAACCCCAACACCCACCGGCACACAGACCCCAACCACGACACCCAUCACCACCAACACCACGGUGACCCCAACCCCGACACCCACCGGCACACAGACCCCAACCACGGUACUCAUCACCACCACCACUACGAUGACACCAACCCCAACACCCACCAGCACAAAGAGUACAACCGUGACACCCAUCACCACCACCACUACUGUGACCCCAACCCCAACACCCACCGGCACACAGAGUACAACCCUGACACCCAUCACCACCACCACUACGGUGACCCCAACCCCAACACCCACCGGCAUACAGACCCCAACAACGACACCCAUCAGCACCACCACCACCGUGACCCCAACCCCAACACCCACCGGCACACAGACCCCAACAUCGACACCCAUCACCACCACCACUACGGUGACCCCAACCCCUACACCCACUGGCACACAGACCCCAACAUCGACACCCAUCAGCACCACCACUACGGUGACCCCAACAGCAACACCCACCGGCACACAGACCCCAACCCUGACACCCAUCACCACCACCACUACGGUGACCCCAACCCCAACACCCACCGGCACAAAGAGUACAACCCCGACAUCCAUCACCACCACCACUACGGUGACCCCAACCCCAACACCCACUGGCACACAGACCCCAACCACGACACCCAUCACCACCACCACCACGGUGACCCCAACCCCAACACCCACCGGCACACAGACCCCAACCCCGACACCCAUCACCACCACCACCACGGUGACCCCAACCCCAACACCCACCAGCACACAGACCCCAACAUCGACACCCAUCACCACCACCACUACGGUGACCCCAACCCCAACACCCACUGGCACACAGACCCCAACCACGACACCCAUUACCACGACCACCACGGUGACCCCAACCCCAACACCCACCGGCACACAGGCCCCAACCCCAACAGCCAUCACCACCACCACUACGGGGACCCCAACCCCAACACCCACCGGCACACAGACCCCAACCACGACACCCAUCACCACCACCACUACGGUGACACCAACCCCAACACCCACCGGCACACAGUCCCCAACCCCAACAGCCAUCACCACCACCACUACGGUGACCCCAACCCCAACACCCACCGGCACACAGACCCCAACCACGACACCCAUCACCACCACCACCACGGUGACCCCAACCCCGACACCCACCGGCACACAGAGUACAACCCUGACACCCAUCACCACCACCACCACGGUGACACCAACCCCAACACCCACUGGCACACAGACCCCAACAUCGACACCCAUCACCACCACCAUUACGGUGACCCCAACCCCAACACCCACCGGCACACAGACCCCAACCCCGACACCCAUCUCCACCACCACUACGGUGACCCCAACCCCAACACCCACCGGCACACAGACCCCAACAUCGACACCCAUCACCACCACCACCACGGUGACCCCAACCCCAACACCCACCGGCACACAGACCCCAACAACGACACCCAUCAGCACCACCACCACGGUGACCCCAACCCCAACACCCACCGGCACACAGACCCCAACAUCGACACCCAUCACCACCACCACCACGGUGACCCCAACCCCAACACCCACCGGCACACAGACCCCAACCACGACACCCAUCAGCACCACCACCACGGUGACCCCAACCCCAACACCCACCGGCACACAGACCCCAACAUCGACACCCAUCACCACCACCACCACGGUGACCCCAACCCCAACACCCACCGGCACACAGACCCCAACCCCGACACCCAUCACCACCACCACCACGGUGACCCCAACCCCAACACCCACCGGCACACAGACCCCAACAUCGACACCCAUCACCACCACCACCACGGUGACCCCAACCCCAACACCCACCGGCACACAGACCCCAACCCCGACACCCAUCACCACCACCACCACGGUGACCCCAACCCCAACACCCACCGGCACACAGACCCCAACCCCGACACCCAUCACCACCACCACCACGGUGACCCCAACCCCAACACCCACCGGCACACAGACCCCAACAUCGACACCCAUCACCACCACCACUACGGUGACCCCAACCCCAACACCCACCGGCACACAGACCCCAACCACGACACCCAUCACCACCACCACCACGGUGACCCCAACCCCAACACCCACUGGCACACAGAGUACAACCCUGACACCCAUCACCACCACCACCACGGUGACACCAACCCCAACACCCACCGGCACACAGACCCCAACAUCGACACCCAUCACCACCAUCACUACGGUGACCCCAACCCCAACACCCACCGGCACACAGACCCCAACCCCGACACCCAUCUCCACCACCACUACAGUGACCCCAACCCCAACACCCACCGGCACACAGACCCCAACCAUGACACCCAUCACCACCACCACCACGGUGACCCCAACCCCAACACCCACCGGCACACAGACCCCAACAACGACACCCAUCAGCACCACCACCACGGUGACCCCAACCCCAACACCCACCGGCACACAGACCCCAACAUCGACACCCAUCACCACCACCACUACGGUGACCCCAACCCCAACACCCACCGGCACACAGACCCCAACCACGACACCCAUCACCACCACCACCACGGUGACCCCAACCCCAACACCCACCGGCACACAGAGUACAACCCUGACACCCAUCACCACCACCACCACGGUGACACCAACCCCAACACCCACCGGCACACAGACCCCAACCCCGACACCCAUCUCCACCACCACUACGGUGACCCCAACCCCAACACCCACCGGCACACAGACCCCAACCAUGACACCCAUCACCACCACCACCACGGUGACCCCAACCCCAACACCCACCGGCACACAGACCCCAACAACGACACCCAUCAGCACCACCACCACGGUGACCCCAACCCCAACACCCACCGGCACACAGACCCCAAGAUCGACACCCAUCACCACCACCACUAAGGUGACCCCAACCCCAACACCCACCGGCACACAGACCCCAACCCCGACACCCAUCACCACCACCACCACGGUGACCCCAACCCCAACACCCACUGGCACACAGGCCCCAACCCCAGCAGCCAUCACCACCACCAGUACGGUGACCCCAACCCCAACACCCACCGGCACACAGACCCCAACCACGACACCCAUCACCACCACCACCACGGUGACCCCAACCCCAACACCCACCGGCACACAGAGUACAACCCUGACACCCAUCACCACCACCACCACGGUGACACCAACCCCAACACCCACCGGCACACAGACCCCAACAUCGACACCCAUCACCACCACCACUACGGUGACCCCAACCCCAACACCCACCGGCACACAGACCCCAACCCCGACACCCAUCUCCACCACCAGUACGGUGACCCCAACCCCAACACCCACCGGCACACAGACCCCAACCAUGACACCCAUCACCACCACCACCACGGUGACCCCAACCCCAACACCCACCGGCACACAGACCCCAACAACGACACCCAUCAGCACCACCACCACGGUGACCCCAACCCCAACACCCACCGGCACACAGAACCCAACAUCGACACCCAUCACCACCACCACUACGGUGACCCCAACCCCAACACCCACCGGCACACAGACCCCAACCAUGACACCCAUCACCACCACCACCACGGUGACCCCAACCCCAACACCCACUGGCACACAGGCCCCAACCCCAACAGCCAUCACCACCACCACUACGGUGACCCCAACCCCAACACCCACCGGCACACAGACCCCAACCACGACACCCAUCACCACCACCACCACGGUGACCCCAACCCCAAUACCCACCGGCACACAGAGUACAACCCUGACACCCAUCACCACCACCACCACGGUGACACCAACCCCAACACCCACCGGCACACAGACCCCAACCCCGAUACCCAUCUCCACCACCACUACGGUGACCCCAACCCCAACACCCACCGGCACACAGACCCCAACCAUGACACCCAUCACCACCACCACCACGGUGACCCCAACCCCAACACCCACCGGCACACAGACCCCAACAACGACACCCAUCAGCACCACCACCACGGUGACCCCAACCCCAACACCCACCGGCACACAGACCCCAACAUCGACACCCAUCACCACCACCACUACGGUGACCCCAACCCCAAUACCCACCGGCACACAGACCCCAACCACGACACCCAUCACCACCACCACCACGGUGACCCCAACCCCAACACCCACUGGCACACAGGCCCCAACCCCAACAGCCAUCACCACCACCACUACGGUGACCCCAACCCCAACACCCACCGGCACACAGACCCCAACCACGACACCCAUCACCACCACCACCACGGUGACCCCAACCCCAAUACCCACCGGCACACAGAGUACAACCCUGACACCCAUCACCACCACCACCACGGUGACACCAACCCCAACACCCACCAGCACACAGACCCCAACCCCGACACCCAUCUCCACCACCACUACGGUGACCCCAACCCCAACACCCACCGGCACACAGACCCCAACCAUGACACCCAUCACCACCACCACCACGGUGACCCCAACCCCAACACCCACCGGCACACAGACCCCAACAACGACACCCAUCAGCACCACCACCACGGUGACCCCAACCCCAACACCCACCGGCACACAGACCCCAACAUCGACACCCAUCACCACCACCACUACAGUGACCCCAACCCCAACAUCCACCGGCACACAGACCCCAACCACGACACCCAUCACCACCACCACCACGGUGACCCCAACCCCAACACCCACUGGCACACAGGCCCCAACCCCAACAGCCAUCACCACCACCAGUACGGUGACCCCAACCCCAACACCCACCGGCACACAGACCCCAACCACGACACCCAUCACCACCACCACUACGGUGACACCAACCCCAACACCCACCGGCACACAGUCCCCAACCCCAACAGCCAUCACCACCACCACUACGGUGACCCCAACCCCAACACCCACCGGCACACAGACCCCAACAUCGACACCCAUCACCACCACCACUACGGUGACCCCAACCCCAACACCCACCGGCACACAGACCCCAACCCCGACACCCAUCUCCACCACCACUACGGUGACCCCAACCCCAACACCCACCGGCACACAGACCCCAACCACGACACCCAUCACCACCACCACCACGGUGACCCCAACCCCGACACCCACCGGCACACAGACCCCAACCACGGUACUCAUCACCACCACCACUACGAUGACCCCAACCCCAACACCCACCAGCACAAAGAGUACAACCGUGACACCCAUCACCACCACAACUACGGUGACCGCAACCCCAACACCCACCGGCACACAGACCCCAACCAUGAUACCCAUCAGCACCACCACUACGGUGACCCCAACCCCAACACCCACCACUGGAAGCACGGGGCCCCCCACCCACACAAGCACAGCACCCAUUGCUGAGUUGACCACAUCCAAUCCUCCGCCUGAGUCCUCAACCCCUCAGACCUCUCGGUCCACCUCUUCCCCUCUCACGGAGUCAACCACCCUUCUGAGUACCCUACCACCUGCCAUUGAGAUGACCAGCACGGCCCCACCCUCCACACCCACGGCACCCACGACCACGAGCGGAGGCCACACACUGUCUCCACCGCCCAGCACCACCACGUCCCCUCCAGGCACCCCCACUCGCGGUACCACGACCGGGUCAUCUUCAGCCCCCACCCCCAGCACUGUGCAGACGACCACCACCAGUGCCUGGACCCCAACGCCGACCCCACUCUCCACACCCAGCAUCAUCAGGACCACAGGCCUGAGGCCCUACCCUUCCUCUGUGCUUAUCUGCUGUGUCCUGAACGACACCUACUACGCACCAGGUGAGGAGGUGUACAACGGCACAUACGGAGACACCUGUUAUUUCGUCAACUGCUCACUGAGCUGUACGUUGGAGUUCUAUAACUGGUCCUGCCCAUCCACGCCCUCCCCAACACCCACGCCCUCCAAGUCGACGCCCACGCCUUCCAAGCCAUCGUCCACGCCCUCCAAGCCGACGCCCGGCACCAAGCCCCCCGAGUGCCCAGACUUUGAUCCUCCCAGACAGGAGAACGAGACUUGGUGGCUGUGCGACUGCUUCAUGGCCACGUGCAAGUACAACAACACGGUGGAGAUCGUGAAGGUGGAGUGUGAGCCGCCGCCCAUGCCCACCUGCUCCAACGGCCUCCAACCCGUGCGCGUCGAGGACCCCGACGGCUGCUGCUGGCACUGGGAGUGCGACUGCUACUGCACGGGCUGGGGCGACCCGCACUAUGUCACCUUCGACGGACUCUACUACAGCUACCAGGGCAACUGCACCUACGUGCUGGUGGAGGAGAUCAGCCCCUCCGUGGACAACUUCGGAGUUUACAUCGACAACUACCACUGCGAUCCCAACGACAAGGUGUCCUGUCCCCGCACCCUCAUCGUGCGCCACGAGACCCAGGAGGUGCUGAUCAAGACCGUGCAUAUGAUGCCCAUGCAGGUGCAGGUGCAGGUGAACAGGCAGGCGGUGGCACUGCCCUACAAGAAGUACGGGCUGGAGGUGUACCAGUCUGGCAUCAACUACGUGGUGGACAUCCCCGAGCUGGGUGUCCUCGUCUCCUACAAUGGCCUGUCCUUCUCCGUCAGGCUGCCCUACCACCGGUUUGGCAACAACACCAAGGGCCAGUGUGGCACCUGCACCAACACCACCUCCGACGACUGCAUUCUGCCCAGCGGGGAGAUCGUCUCCAACUGUGAGGCUGCGGCUGACCAGUGGCUGGUGAACGACCCCUCCAAGCCACACUGCCCCCACAGCAGCUCCACGACCAAGCGCCCGGCCGUCACUGUGCCCGGGGGCGGUAAAACGACCCCACACAAGGACUGCACCCCAUCUCCCCUCUGCCAGCUCAUCAAGGACAGCCUGUUUGCCCAGUGCCACGCACUGGUGCCCCCGCAGCACUACUACGAUGCCUGCGUGUUCGACAGCUGCUUCAUGCCGGGCUCGAGCCUGGAGUGCGCCAGUCUGCAGGCCUACGCAGCCCUCUGUGCCCAGCAGAACAUCUGCCUCGACUGGCGGAACCACACGCAUGGGGCCUGCUUGGUGGAGUGCCCAUCUCACAGGGAGUACCAGGCCUGUGGCCCUGCAGAAGAGCCCACGUGCAAAUCCAGCUCCUCCCAGCAGAACAACACAGUCCUGGUGGAAGGCUGCUUCUGUCCUGAGGGCACCAUGAACUACGCUCCUGGCUUUGAUGUCUGCGUGAAGACCUGCGGCUGUGUGGGACCUGACAAUGUGCCCAGAGAGUUUGGGGAGCACUUCGAGUUCGACUGCAAGAACUGUGUCUGCCUGGAGGGUGGAAGUGGCAUCAUCUGCCAACCCAAGAGGUGCAGCCAGAAGCCCGUUACCCACUGCGUGGAAGACGGCACCUACCUCGCCACGGAGGUCAACCCUGCCGACACCUGCUGCAACAUUACCGUCUGCAAGUGCAACACCAGCCUGUGCAAAGAGAAGCCCUCCGUGUGCCCGCUGGGAUUCGAAGUGAAGAGCAAGAUGGUGCCUGGAAGGUGCUGUCCUUUCUACUGGUGUGAGUCCAAGGGGGUGUGUGUUCACGGGAAUGCUGAGUACCAGCCCGGUUCUCCAGUUUAUUCCUCCAAGUGCCAGGACUGCGUGUGCACGGACAAGGUGGACAACAACACCCUGCUCAACGUCAUCGCCUGCACCCACGUGCCCUGCAACACCUCCUGCAGCCCUGGCUUCGAACUCAUGGAGGCCCCCGGGGAGUGCUGUAAGAAGUGUGAACAGACGCACUGUAUCAUCAAACGGCCCGACAACCAGCACGUCAUCCUGAAGCCCGGGGACUUCAAGAGCGACCCGAAGAACAACUGCACAUUCUUCAGCUGCGUGAAGAUCCACAACCAGCUCAUCUCGUCCGUCUCCAACAUCACCUGCCCCAACUUUGAUGCCAGCAUUUGCAUCCCGGGCUCCAUCACAUUCAUGCCCAAUGGAUGCUGCAAGACCUGCACCCCUCGCAAUGAGACCAGGGUGCCCUGCUCCACCGUCCCCGUCACCACGGAGGUUUCGUACGCCGGCUGCACCAAGACCGUCCUCAUGAAUCAUUGCUCCGGGUCCUGCGGGACAUUUGUCAUGUACUCGGCCAAGGCCCAGGCCCUGGACCACAGCUGCUCCUGCUGCAAAGAGGAGAAAACCAGCCAGCGUGAGGUGGUCCUGAGCUGCCCCAAUGGCGGCUCGCUGACACACACCUACACCCACAUCGAGAGCUGCCAGUGCCAGGACACCGUCUGCGGGCUCCCCACCGGCACCUCCCGCCGGGCCCGGCGCUCCCCUAGGCAUCUGGGGAGCGGGUGAGCGGGGUGGGCACAGCCCCCUUCACUGCCCUCGACAGCUUUACCUCCCCCGGACCCUCUGAGCCUCCUAAGCUCGGCUUCCUCUCUUCAGAUAUUUAUUGUCUGAGUCUUUGUUCAGUCCUUGCUUUCCAAUAAUAAACUCAGGGGGACAUGC